AGCAGCGCGCGCUCCUGCAGCCCCGGCGGAGUCCCGGCGGGGAGCGCCCGCGUAGGCAGGCACCCGGGGCAGCCCUCCGUCCUCGCCGCGCGGCCUGAGAACCCCUGGGCCCUGGGCGAGGGGGCUGGGCUGUGCAGCCCCCGAGGCUAACUGGGCGGGAUCGCAGCUGCAGGGGUUGUGCGAGCAGCCACGGCGGCACCUGUGCCCUGCGGGCACCCACCCUGCCCCUGCCGAGGCAGGCGCCCACCGCCGGCGGUGAUGCGGCUGUGAAGCCCUAGUCGAUUAACGUGACAGUGUCAGGUGGACCCACAGCCAUCCCACCUCCCCCUCUGGGGAGUGCUGAGAGUGAGGCAGCAUGGAGGAGAGGAAGCAUGAGACCAUGAACCCAGCUCAUGUCCUCUUUGACCGGUUUGUCCAGGCCACCACCUGCAAGGGAACCCUCAAGGCUUUCCAGGAGCUCUGUGACCACCUGGAACUAAAGCCAAAGGACUACCGCUCCUUCUAUCACAAGCUCAAGUCCAAGCUUAACUACUGGAAAGCCAAAGCCCUCUGGGCAAAAUUGGACAAACGGGGCAGUCACAAAGACUACAAAAAGGGAAAAGCGUGCACUAACACCAAGUGUCUCAUCAUUGGGGCUGGCCCCUGUGGUCUCCGUACAGCCAUCGACUUAUCCUUACUGGGGGCCAAGGUGGUUGUUAUUGAGAAACGAGAUGCCUUCUCCCGCAACAACGUCUUGCAUCUCUGGCCAUUCACCAUACAUGAUCUACGAGGUCUGGGUGCCAAGAAGUUCUAUGGCAAGUUCUGUGCUGGAGCCAUCGACCAUAUCAGUAUCCGUCAGCUCCAACUAAUACUUUUGAAAGUAGCCUUGAUCCUAGGCAUUGAAAUCCACGUCAAUGUGGAAUUCCAAGGACUUAUACAGCCUCCUGAGGACCAAGAGAAUGAACGGAUAGGCUGGCGGGCACUGGUGCACCCCAAGACUCAUCCUGUGUCAGAGUAUGAAUUUGAAGUGAUCAUCGGUGGGGAUGGUCGGAGGAACACCUUGGAAGGGUUUCGUCGGAAAGAAUUCCGUGGCAAACUGGCCAUCGCCAUCACGGCAAAUUUUAUCAACCGAAAUACAACAGCAGAAGCUAAAGUGGAAGAGAUCAGUGGUGUGGCUUUUAUAUUCAACCAAAAAUUUUUCCAGGAACUGAGGGAAGCCACAGGUAUUGACUUGGAGAACAUCGUUUACUACAAAGAUGACACACACUAUUUCGUUAUGACAGCCAAAAAGCAGAGUUUGCUGGACAAAGGAGUGAUACUACAUGACUACGCCGACACAGAGCUCCUGCUUUCCCGAGAAAACGUGGACCAGGAGGCUCUGCUCAGCUAUGCCAGGGAGGCGGCAGACUUCUCUACCCAGCAGCAGCUGCCGUCUCUGGAUUUUGCCAUCAAUCACUAUGGGCAGCCCGAUGUGGCCAUGUUUGACUUCACUUGUAUGUAUGCCUCCGAGAACGCCGCCUUGGUGCGGGAGCAGAACGGACACCAGUUACUAGUGGCUCUGGUCGGGGACAGCCUCCUAGAGCCUUUCUGGCCAAUGGGAACAGGAAUAGCCCGGGGCUUUCUAGCUGCUAUGGACUCUGCCUGGAUGGUCCGAAGUUGGUCUCUAGGAACGAGCCCUUUGGAAGUGCUGGCAGAGAGGGAAAGUAUUUACAGGUUGCUGCCUCAGACCACCCCUGAGAAUGUGAGUAAGAACUUCAGCCAGUACAGUAUCGACCCUGUCACUCGGUAUCCCAAUAUCAACGUCAACUUCCUCCGGCCAAGCCAGGUGCGCCAUUUAUAUGAUACUGGCGAAACAAAAGAUAUUCACCUGGAAAUGGAGAGCCUGGUGAAUUCCCGAACCACCCCCAAAUUGACUCGCAAUGAGUCUGUAGCUCGUUCAAGCAAACUGCUGGGUUGGUGCCAGAGGCAGACAGAUGGCUAUGCAGGGGUAAACGUGACAGAUCUCACCAUGUCCUGGAAAAGUGGCUUGGCCCUUUGUGCAAUUAUCCAUAGAUACCGCCCUGACCUGAUAGAUUUUGAUUCUUUGGAUGAGCAAAAUGUGGAGAAGAAUAACCAACUGGCCUUUGACAUUGCUGAGAAGGAAUUGGGCAUUUCUCCCAUCAUGACAGGCAAAGAAAUGGCCUCCGUGGGGGAGCCUGAUAAGCUGUCCAUGGUGAUGUACCUGACUCAGUUCUACGAGAUGUUUAAGGACUCCCUCCCCUCUAGCGACACCUUGGACCUAAAUGCCGAGGAGAAAGCAGUCCUGAUAGCCAGCACCAGAUCCCCUAUCUCCUUCCUAAGCAAACUUGGCCAGACCAUCUCUCGGAAGCGUUCUCCCAAGGAUAAAAAGGAAAAGGACUUGGAUGGUGCUGGGAAGAGGAGAAAGACCAGUCAAUCAGAGGAGGAGGAAGCUCCUCGGGGCCACAGAGGAGAAAGACCGACCCUGGUGAGCACUCUGACAGACAGGAGGAUGGACGUUGCCGUUGGGAACCAGAACAAAGUGAAGUACAUGGCGACCCAGCUGCUGGCCAAAUUUGAAGAGAAUGCGCCCGCACAGUCCAUCGGCAUACGGAGACAGGGCUCCAUGAAGAAGGAGUUCCCGCAGAACCUGGGAGGCAGCGACACAUGCUACUUCUGCCAGAAGCGGGUCUACGUGAUGGAGAGGCUGAGUGCCGAGGGCAAGUUCUUCCACCGGAGCUGCUUCAAGUGCGAGUACUGCGCCACCACCCUGCGCCUCUCGGCCUACGCCUACGACAUCGAGGAUGGUAAAUUCUACUGUAAGCCACACUACUGCUAUCGACUCUCUGGCUACGCACAAAGGAAGAGACCGGCAGUGGCUCCCCUGUCUGGAAAGGAGGCCAAAGGACCCCUGCAGGAUGGCGCCACCACAGAUGCAAACGGACGGGCCAACGCCGUGGCCAGCUCCACUGAGAGAACCCCAGGUUCAGGCGUGAACGGCCUGGAGGAGCCCAGCAUCGCCAAGCGACUGAGGGGCACCCCAGAGCGGAUCGAGCUGGAGAACUACCGCCUGUCCCUGAGGCAGGCUGAGGCACUGCAGGAGGUACCGGAGGAGACUCAGGCCGAGCACAACCUGAGCAGCGUGCUGGACACGGGCGCCGAGGAGGACGUCGCCAGCAGUAGUUCCGAGUCUGAGAUGGAGGAGGAGGGAGAGGAGGAGGAGGAGGAGCCUCGCCUGCCCCCAUCUGACCUGGGUGGUGUUCCGUGGAAGGAGGCCGUGCGGAUCCAUGCCCUUCUGAAAGGGAAAAGUGAAGAGGAGCUAGAGGCCUCAAAGAGCUUUGGGCCUGGGAAUGAAGAGGAGGAGGAGGAGGAGGAAGAAUAUGAAGAGGAGGAGGAGGAGGACUAUGACGAGGAGGAGGAAGAGUCCAGUGAAGCCGGGAACCAGAGGCUCCAGCAGGUCAUGCACGCGGCGGAUCCUCUGGAGAUCCAGGCUGACGUGCACUGGACUCAUAUCCGUGAGAGAGAGGAGGAAGAGAGGAUGGCGCCGGCCUCUGAGUCCUCUGCUUCCGGAGCCCCAUUGGAUGAGAAUGACCUAGAGGAAGAUGUGGACUCAGAACCAGCCGAGAUAGAAGGGGAGGCAGCAGAGGAUGGGGACCCAGGGGACACUGGUGCUGAGCUGGAUGAUGAUCAGCACUGGUCUGACAGCCCGUCGGAUGCUGACAGAGAGCUGCGUUUGCCGUGCCCAGCUGAGGGGGAAGCAGAGCUGGAGCUGAGGGUGUCGGAAGAUGAGGAGAAGCUGCCCGCCUCACCGAAGCACCAAGAGAGAGGUCCCUCCCAAGCCACCAGCCCCAUCCGGUCUCCCCAGGAAUCAGCUCUUCUGUUCAUUCCAGUCCACAGCCCCUCAACAGAGGGGCCCCAACUCCCACCUGUCCCUGCCGCCACCCAGGAGAAAUCACCUGAGGAGCGCCUUUUCCCUGAGCCUUUGCUCCCCAAAGAGAAGCCCAAAGCUGAUGCCCCCUCGGAUCUGAAAGCUGUGCACUCUCCCAUCCGAUCACAGCCAGUGACCCUGCCAGAAGCUAGGACUCCUGUCUCACCAGGGAGCCCGCAGCCCCAGCCACCCGUGGCGGCCUCCACGCCCCCACCCAGCCCACUCCCCAUCUGCUCCCAGCCCCAGCCUUCCACCGAGGCCACUGUCCCAUCCCCUACCCAGUCCCCCAUACGCUUCCAGCCUGCCCCGGCCAAAACAUCCACCCCACUGGCCCCUCUCCCUGUCCAAAGCCAAAGUGACACCAAGGACAGACUGGGCAGCCCCCUUGCUGUGGAUGAGGCCCUCAGACGGAGCGACCUGGUGGAGGAGUUCUGGAUGAAGAGUGCGGAGAUCCGCCGCAGCCUCGGGCUCACACCUGUGGACCGCAGCAAGGGGCCCGAGCCCAGCUUCCCCACGCCUGCCUUCAGGCCAGUGUCCCUCAAAUCCUAUUCCGUUGAAAAGUCCCCCCAGGAUGAGGGACUCCACCUUCUCAAGCCUCUGUCCAUCCCCAAAAGGCUGGGCCUGCCAAAGCCGGAAGGCGAGCCGUUGUCCCUGCCAACCCCCCGGUCCCCGUCCGACAGAGAGCUACGCAGCGCCCAGGAGGAGCGCAGGGAGCUGUCCAGCAGCUCUGGCCUGGGCCUGCACGGGAGCUCCUCCAACAUGAAGACACUGGGCAGCCAGAGCUUCAACACCUCGGACUCCGCCAUGCUCACGCCCCCCUCCAGCCCGCCCCCACCGCCACCCCCGGGCGAGGAGCCCGCCACCUUGCGGAGGAAGCUCAGGGAGGCCGAGCCCAAUGCCUCGGUGGUCCCGCCGCCCUUGCCCGCCACCUGGAUGCGGCCCCCCCGGGAGCCUGCUCAGCCCCCCAGAGAGGAGGUGCGGAAGUCGUUUGUGGAGAGCGUGGAGGAGAUUCCCUUUGCUGAUGAUGUGGAGGACACCUAUGACGACAAGACUGAGGACUCAAGCCUGCAGGAGAAAUUCUUCACGCCCCCGUCCUGCUGGCCGCGCCCCGAGAAGCCUCGCCACCCGCCCCUGGCCAAGGAGAACGGGAGGCUGCCUGCUCUGGAGGGGACGCUGCAGCCACAGAAGAGGGGGCUGCCCUUGGUGUCCGCGGAAGCCAAGGAGUUGGCCGAGGAGCGCAUGCGAGCCAGGGAGAAGUCCGUGAAGAGCCAGGCGCUGCGGGACGCCAUGGCCAGGCAGCUGAGCAGGAUGCAGCAGAUGGAGCUGGCCUCAGGCGCCCCCAGGCCCCGCAAGGCGUCCUCAGCACCCUCCCAGGGCAAGGAGCGCCGGCCUGACUCCCCCACACGCCCCACUCUCAGGGGCUCCGAGGAGCCCACCCUGAAGCAUGAAGCCACCAGCGAGGAGGUCCUCUCCCCGCCGUCGGACUCAGGGGGCCCAGAUGGCUCUUUCACUUCAUCCGAGGGCUCCAGUGGGAAGAGCAAGAAGAGGUCGUCACUCUUCUCCCCCCGCAGAAACAAGAAGGAGAAGAAGUCCAAAGGCGAGGGCCGGCCCCCGGAGAAGCCCAGCUCCAACCUCCUAGAAGAAGCCGCCGCCAAACCCAAGUCCCUGUGGAAGUCCGUCUUCUCCGGGUACAAGAAGGACAAGAAGAAGAAGGCCGACGACAAGUCCUGCCCCAGCACCCCCUCCAGCGGGGCCACGGUGGACUCUGGAAAGCACAGGGUGCUUCCCGUCGUAAGGGCAGAGCUGCAGCUCCGGCGCCAGCUGAGCUUCUCCGAGGACUCAGACCUCUCCAGCGACGAUGUCCUUGAGAAGUCCUCACAGAAGUCCCGGCGAGAGCCAAGAACCUACACGGAGGAGGAACUGAAUGCCAAGCUGACCCGGCGUGUGCAAAAGGCAGCUCGGAGACAGGCCAAGCAGGAGGAGCUUAAGCGGCUGCAUCGAGCCCAGAUCAUCCAGCGGCAGCUGCAGCAGGUGGAGGAGAGGCAGCGGCGGCUGGAGGAAAGGGGCGUGGCUGUGGAGAAGGCGCUCCGGGGCGAAGCAGGCAUGGGCAAGAAGGACGACCCCAAGCUGAUGCAGGAGUGGUUCAAGCUAGUGCAGGAGAAGAACGCCAUGGUGCGCUACGAGUCGGAGCUGAUGAUCUUUGCCCGGGAGCUGGAGCUGGAAGACCGGCAGAGUCGACUGCAGCAGGAGCUCCGGGAACGCAUGGCAGUGGAAGAUCACCUUAAGACUGAGGAGGAGCUGUCAGAAGAGAAGCAGAUUCUCAAUGAGAUGCUGGAGGUGGUGGAGCAGAGAGACUCACUGGUGGCGCUGCUGGAGGAGCAGCGGCUCCGGGAGAGAGAGGAGGACAAGGACCUGGAGGCUGCCAUGCUGUCCAAGGGCUUCAGCCUUAACUGGUCCUGAGCUCCCACCCAACGCUCCAUUUUCUGUUGGCAUCCGCCUGGCCAGGCAGUGGCAUCCAAACCACCCGGAGCCGCGAUCUGAGGAGGCCUGGCACCUCCUUGGAGUUUACGCUCAGAUGCCCGUGUGCUGCUUGGAAAGUGGUCGAGUCCCGCGUGCAGUGGGGAGCCCCAGGUGACAGUGGUUAUCUGAGACGGCUCCACCUCCUGGGAGGAGGCCCACCUGGACCUCCCACUCAGAGGAGCAGCACGGCGUGUAUGGCAUGACGCAGGGGACCACCCCGCGCGCUCCCUGAGGAUGUGCUGGCUGUGCCCCUUUUUUCCACUGGCACAUUUGGUAAGAGAGGGAAGCUGCUCCCCGUCAGAACCACAGUGCGCCGUGCGAGGGGCACUGUCUUCUUCAUGCUCCCUGGAGCACCACCAAAGAAACGUAAACAAUACCCCACGAAAGCAGGGUCAGGGGUCAGGGUGCGAUCGAGACCCAGGAUGGGGGCGUCCAGUCAUGCCCACCCCAGCAUCACAGGAGACAUGGAGGUGCGGGCAGGCUCCUGAAUUAUUAUGCAAAUUAGGAGGACGCAGGAGGGGUCUGCCCUCCAGCCGAACACCACACACUGGACCCUAAGUGGCCAAAUGCCUGGGCCGCUUGCUGGCUGUGGCCUGAGGCUUGUGGGUUGCUGCAUUUUGCUUGUAGUUCACAACCAUUUUGACACUGGAAAAUGCUGACUUUGGGGGACAGGAUGAGGCCCUACAUUCUAAGCCCCCAGUUGGCAGACAGGCAUUGUCCCUGUUCCACAUUUAUGUCGGGACAGGAGAUGACCUUUUCCUCCGUGUUUUUCCUGUGUUUGCACGUUGAAAUGAAGCUGACAACCUGGCAAGACGCUCAGCCGCUUCAAACCCUUUUUGUCAAUUAACUUAUUUUUUAAUACUUGAAAAGAAGUAACUUCGUUUGUGUAUCUUUACUAGAGGAACUGAUCACCUGCGCCCGGGUGCGGGAGCCACAGCGGCAUCUGGUGCGUCCUACGCGACCUGGUCCGGGGCUGCCCGGUGCUCCUCACGUGCAUCUAUUUAUUAGCCUUUCUCUUCGUAUCACUGGCCUGGCUGGCAUCAGGGAGCUGCCCAGAACCCCUGUGUGGGUCCUCCUCACAGCUUUCUGUCCCCUCCUCCACCCGGUGCCUGCCUCACCCUGGCGCUAGACCAUCUGGACCACUCAUGUGAUGAGGGUGCAUUUCCGUUCUGUUUUGGGCCAGGCCAACAGCAGAGCUGCCACUCUCACCCUCCCAGUGAGAAUUCCGGCUCUGCAGAACUCGCCCUUGUCUCAGUUUGGGGGCCAGGGCAUCACCUUCCUCCGCACAUAUGUUAAAGAAGGUUUCAGGAUGGGCCCUCAUCCACACAGGCCAAGAGGGUGCAAGGUGGGACCCUGGAAUCAUGUGGCUGGUGAGAAUUCCCUCCUCCCAGCCUAAGAUUCACCCAGACGGAAACGCGAGUGCUGCAGUGGAUGCUGGGAUGCAGGCUGGUGCCUCUCAAGCAGAUCAGCGACUCCCGCCCUUCCUUCCGAAGGCGACGGGCACCUGCCUUGUGCCGGAUCUUCAUGGGGACAUAAAGGGCGAGCCCCGAAUCACUAGCUCCUAUAGCCAAACUGUUCCUUUCUCACGGUUCCGCACCAGCCUGGCUGUGUACAGCUCAUCAAGCCACUGAGCUAAUCGGGGUGGGGUGCUUGUCCAUCAAAGCAGUCAGCACAUAGCCCAGCGAGGAGCCAUCCGGACCAGACCCGCCUGCCAGGGGCGCUCCAGCCGCCUGCCGCCUCCGUGGGCUGGGGCCAGCUGGGAGCAGAGGCCUGGCCCCUCCAAGGCGUCCCGCAGUGGAGCAGGCUGAGUGGCUGUGCUGACCUUGGGCUUUCCAUGGGAACCACACUGUGCUUCAACUUGAACAUUCAUCCCAGCUGCAAAGGAGCAAAGAACCUGUGUCAUCCUUGUCUGUCCAGAAGCUGCCAUCUCUCUCCCAUGCACAUCCGGGAGAUAACGCCGCUAGUGGCCGCCACAGCGCUGAUUCUCCACCUGUUCUCACGUGAGGCAAAGGUCUCCUUUUCUUUUCUCUUUACUUAAAAAAGGGGAGAGGAGGGUUUCUAGAUUCCAUCUUCAAACCCCAGUCGUCCCAUAAAAUUGGACGUGGGAAAAGACCUUCACUGCCUGCGUGGCCUUUCCCAGACCUCUCCUCGAAUGCCACAAAACCGGUCCAGCCCCGGCAGAGCCGCCUUCGGCCCUUGUAGCUCCUGCUGGCCCCACAACAGGGAAACAGUUUGCAAAGUGGCUUGGAAGGAGUGUGGCCUAGGGAUCUGCUGUAAGUGGCCAGACGUAGCAGGAGAGCCCAGUGUCACCUUCUGGUCCUGGUCAGCCUUAACACUGUGGCAUCCUCCACAGCACACACGGCAGCCUGCAGUCUGGAAGGUGGACCCGAGCCUUUGCAGAGAGGCGCCGCAGAGCCGCAGGCCUGCGCCCCAGCCUUCUGCUCCCGACUGUGAGGACACCCAGUUCUAGUAGAGCACUUUUUUUAAAGCUCCCAUUUUGUAACCACUAGUUUGCGGUUGACUUGAGUACUCUGGUGACUUCCUGCGUCAAGCGUUCUCAAGCUGUGAGAAUGUGCGCAGCUCCAGGCAGGUUUUCUCUCGGAGAGUUAAGUCUUCCCUUGAAGGCAGGGAAGCAGGAUGGAUACACAUAUAUCACACGCAUAAAACACCAGGUGCGGGAGCAGCCCAGACUCAAGGCUGACUAAACUGGAGGCUGAAUACCGUGGAGGUCCACAUGCAGCUUCCCUGGAGGGCAGGCCGGAGGCGCUCCCGCCCCUGGGCUUGAGGAUGCUGCACCCCGUGGGCUUCCAGGCCUGCCCAGAUGAUGCCUUCAGGCCUCUGUCCCUGGCGGCCAUCCUCAGGCCGAUUUUGACCAGCAAUGAUAGACUCUUCUUAACCCUUUCAAAAUAAAUUUUUCAGUGGGACAGAAAGGAGAGUUAAAAAACAUUUUUUUAAAGGUGGUAACAUCUGACCCACAAAGGGAAUGGGUCUGUUUUAUGCAAAAUAAAAGUUUUUCAAAUAAA